GGCUGCUGCAGCCCGGGCGGCUGCCGAGAAGGAGGGAGGGGAAACACAAAGCCGGCUACGCGCUGCGAGGUAAUCUUGCGGGGAGAGGACGCGCCGUCGUCCCGCCUCUCUUCCGGGCCGGGACGCGGGCACCCGCGCGGGGGCUAGCACUGGGGACGCUACUGGGGGUCGCGCGGGGGUAGGGAGCGGCGGCUGGCGGGGCCAAGGGGACUUCUCAUUGGCUGUCCCUGCGGCCUCAGGUGAACCCUUUUCCGGGGCGGGAGUGGGGACCACGGCCAGGCCAGAGGGGAGCGUACCUGCGGGGGAGGGUCCGGGGGUGGCGGUGCACGGCCUGCGGCGCCGCCGGGUGGGCCCGACGCUUCGCGCGUCUGCUGGUUUUCCCUAGGAAGGCGGGGAGUACCAAAAUCAGUUACUGGCUGAAGCUUAGGUGACCCCGGGGACCUUAAGCCCUGAAGGUGCGCUCCAGGGGAGUGAGAGGUUCCUGCGCUUAGAAAAGGUGGAGGAAAGGGAGCGAAUGUUGGUUUUAGUUGUUUUUCUCCUCAUUUAAAAAAAAUUUUUUUUGUUACAAGUUGAAAGUGUUCAGUCACCUUUCUCCUAUAAUCCGCUUCCCCACCCCCCAACACAGACACACACAAACACACCGCCCCUACAAACGUAUACAUGUUAGGUUGAGCUUCCUGCUAGGGGUGACAAGCGAAGUUGGCAGCAGGUCUGGUGUGCUGGUGUUUGGGGCACGUCCAGCCUCUUUGGAGAGUUGUCUCCCAGAGCUCCGUGGAAUUUCCUUUCUCUGCUUUAACGUACUUUUAAAAGAUAACAAGAGUAAUCCACAGACUUAAAACAUGAGCUCAGAUGCCAGCCAAGGCGUGAUUACCACUCCUCCUCCUCCCAGCAUGCCUCACAAAGAGAGAUAUUUUGACCGCAUCAAUGAAAAUGACCCAGAAUACAUUAGGGAGAGGAACAUGUCUCCUGAUCUACGACAAGACUUCAACAUGAUGGAGCAGAGGAAACGAGUUACUCAGAUCCUGCAAAGUCCUGCCUUUCGGGAAGACUUGGAAUGCCUUAUUCAAGAACAGAUGAAGAAAGGCCACAACCCAACUGGAUUACUAGCAUUACAGCAGAUUGCAGAUUACAUCAUGGCCAAUUCUUUCUCGGGUUUUUCUUCACCUCCUCUCAGUCUUGGCAUGGUCACACCUAUCAAUGACCUUCCUGGUGCAGAUACAUCCUCAUAUGUGAAGGGAGAAAAACUUACUCGCUGUAAACUUGCCAGCCUGUACAGACUUGUAGACUUGUUUGGAUGGGCACACCUGGCAAAUACCUAUAUCUCAGUAAGAAUAAGUAAGGAGCAAGACCACAUUAUAAUAAUUCCCAGAGGCCUAUCUUUUUCUGAAGCUACAGCCUCCAAUUUGGUGAAAGUCAAUAUAAUAGGAGAAGUGGUUGACCAGGGAAGUACCAAUUUGAAAAUUGACCAUACAGGAUUCAGUCCCCAUGCUGCAAUCUAUUCAACACGUCCUGAUGUUAAGUGUGUGAUACACAUCCAUACCCUUGCAACAGCAGCUGUAUCCUCCAUGAAAUGUGGGAUCCUUCCAAUUUCUCAAGAGUCUCUUCUUCUGGGAGAUGUUGCCUAUUAUGACUACCAAGGGUCACUUGAAGAACAGGAGGAGAGAAUUCAACUGCAGAAGGUUCUGGGACCAAGUUGUAAGGUGCUGGUACUCAGGAAUCAUGGUGUGGUUGCACUUGGAGAAACAUUAGAGGAGGCUUUUCAUUAUAUUUUUAAUGUGCAACUAGCCUGUGAGAUUCAGGUGCAGGCCCUAGCAGGUGCAGGUGGAGUAGACAAUCUCCAUGUACUGGACUUUCAGAAGUAUAAAGCUUUCACUUACACUGUAGCAGCGUCUGGUGGAGGAGGUGUGAAUAUGGGUUCCCAUCAAAAAUGGAAGGUUGGCGAAAUUGAGUUUGAAGGGCUUAUGAGGACUCUGGACAACUUGGGGUAUAGAACAGGCUAUGCUUACAGGCAUCCUCUCAUUCGAGAGAAGCCUAGGCACAAGAGUGAUGUGGAAAUCCCAGCAACUGUGACUGCUUUUUCCUUUGAAGACGAUACAGUGCCACUCUCUCCUCUCAAAUACAUGGCACAGAGGCAACAGCGUGAAAAAACAAGAUGGCUGAACUCACCAAAUACUUACAUGAAAGUGAAUGUGCCUGAGGAGUCUCGGAACGGAGAAACCAGUCCCCGAACCAAAAUCACGUGGAUGAAAGCAGAAGACUCAUCUAAAGUUAGUGGUGGAACACCUAUCAAAAUUGAAGAUCCAAAUCAGUUUGUUCCUUUAAACACAAACCCGAAUGAGGUACUAGAAAAGAGAAAUAAGAUUCGGGAACAAAAUCGAUAUGACUUGAAAACAGCAGGACCACAAUCUCAGUUGCUUGCUGGAAUUGUUGUGGAUAAGCCACCUUCUACUAUGCAAUUUGAAGAUGAUGAUCAUGGCCCACCAGCUCCUCCUAACCCAUUUAGUCAUCUCACAGAAGGAGAACUUGAAGAGUAUAAGAGGACAAUCGAACGUAAACAACAAGGCCUAGAAGAUGCUGAGCAGGAAUUACUCUCAGAUGACGCUUCAUCUGUUUCACAAAUUCAGUCUCAAACUCAGUCACCGCAAAAUGUCCCUGAAAAAUUAGAAGAAAACCAUGAGCUGUUUUCCAAGAGCUUCAUCUCCAUGGAAGUGCCUGUCAUGGUAGUAAAUGGCAAGGAUGAUAUGCAUGAUGUUGAAGAUGAGCUUGCUAAGCGAGUGAGUAGGUUAAGCACAAGUACAACCAUAGAAAACAUCGAGAUUACUAUUAAGUCUCCAGAGAAAAUCGAAGAAGUCCUGUCACCUGAAGGCUCCCCUUCAAAAUCGCCAUCCAAGAAAAAGAAGAAAUUCCGCACUCCUUCUUUUCUGAAAAAGAACAAAAAAAAGGAGAAAGUUGAGGCCUAAAUAAAGUCUUUUUAUAAUUAUUAUUAUAACAAUGUGACAUUGCACAUCUAAAUACCACAUUUAAGUUGAUCAUUAAUAUGCAAUGGUAGAUCAGAUUGGGGGAUGUAGCAAACUGGACUUUAAGAACUGGAAAGAGGUUUUACAAAAGAAAAACUUUCAGAUUCAUCUCUCAUUUUAUAUGUCCAGAAAUGGCUUUGAAUUUUAAGCAAUUACUAGUUUUAAUUAGCUCUGCCCUCAUGAAGUAUUAUUAUAAUUCACCAUAAACAGCUAUCUGUCUGAAUUACUUCAGGCCUUCUCCAUAAUAUCUGUUAGAAAGAAAUUGCCAGUGAGCAAGUGAGAAUUUUUAUUUCUCAAUACCUGCUUCACUUGAUAAUCAUAUUAUAAUUUUUUAUCAUGAUUAUUGACUAUAUUUUUGGAGUCCCAUUGUUUCAGUGGGCAUUAACAGAAUGCUUUAAAAACUUCUAAGACAAGAAUCUAUAGCAUUAGUAUACACUGGCACAUAAUUUUUUAAAAAGUUUUAAGAAAAGAUUCAUUUGGAAUUUUAUUCACAGUAUAAAAUUUCCUCACCUGAAGUAACUUUGUUUGCCAAAAAAGUUGUUUUAAUAAACUAUAAUUUUUGAAAACUUCCUUUUUUAUUAGUUUAGAAAGCCCCUUAUUUUUCAACAAAGGGGAUUUUGUACACAUAACAUGGGUUAUUUAGUUUAACUCUGGCAAAAAAAAAAAAAAAAAUUUUGUAUGUUGAUGUUUGUAUACCGUUCAGUAUAAAAGUGUCCUAAGCAUAUUAGCCAAUCUUUUCACAGUAGAGCAUACUUAAGGCUGCUUGGUACUGAGUAUACUUAAAUAUAACUCCAGAAUCCAGGGACUUGGUGUUAAAACAGGAUUAGAGCAUGUAAAGGUACAUCUAGAUUCAUAUUUGAAUCUUAAACUGUAUUUUUCUCUUAGUAUUGCUAAUGAGUAAAGAAAAGUCUCAUAAGGUAGCCAAAUGAAAAAGAAUGAAAGGGAAAGUGAAAAAUUAAGGGGACAAAAGAUGGGAUGUGAAAAGAAGAAUUCUAGUUUGAUGGUGACUCAUAUUCACGAUAGGAUACAAAGUGUGAUUUGUUGGAAACAUGUCCCAAAUUUCUAAAAUUCUGCUUCUCUGCCAAAAGCAAUGUCUUUCUUGGUUGAUAUUUGAGUUUUAAAAGGGUCAAAUCUUUCUAAUUUUUUGUAUCUUUAGAGGGCAGCACUAGAAGAAAUCAGCAGGUCUAAUCCCACCAGUAAGAAAACUACCACUUCUUGAUUUUUACAGAUUUAAAAAAAUCUUUUCAGUGACCUUUCUUUUUAAUGUAAAUACAAAUUUAAACCUAGGCUUAAUAUAGGCGUUUCCCCUUUCACCCAAGUGAUGUCACAGUUCGAUGCAAAAUCAAUGAUCCAGAAUGAUCGUGGGUAAAAAUAACUCAAAGUGUUUCUUAAGGGUGAGUUGGCAUGCAAAAAAUUACAUUGAUUACAGUGUGUUUUGGAGCUGGCUCUGUUUGUGUGCAUAUGAUAAUGCAGAGUUGAGCCAGAGCCUGGAAAUGUCAUUCUAGAUCUCACUAACUACUGGAAUCAGUGUUUUAAUCUCUUGGUGGAAACUUUCAGUUGCUUAACUCUCUAUUGGAAGAUUUUUUUAAUGUUCUACAUCAUUUAUGUUGUAUUACAAUGUAUGUAGAAAUAGUAACCUGUGAACUAUGCUUUUCCAUAACUUUUUAAAAAUAUAUAUAUCUAAAUGAAUGCAAUGUGCAUAAAUAUUUUUUAAACAUAACAGUGAACUAUUGCACCUUUUGCUAAUGCCUCUAUUUACUUGCUUUGGCAUAAAGAAUGAGCCAAUGAACCUCUGUGUCCUGUGGAAAAAUGUAUAAAUGUUAUCUGAUAUUGCUCUUAGAUGUAAUGCUAAUUAAUGUUAAAUCACAAAUAAACAGUAUUUUAAAUAUA